GUUUCACUUAGAGCCACAGUUUCCAAGAACCCGUAAGGACUUUACUGUAUCUGAAAACCUGGUUAGCUCCUAACUGGAGUAACUGGGUUAAAGAAGCAUUUGAACAUUAUUUGUUGAACCAGAUCAAAGAACAUUGCUACUUUAGGGUAUUUUCUGGAACUGAAAUAACUAGAUCCAUUUCUGUUUUUAUAUUCAUUGUAAUGGCAUUGGACUUGUAUAGCAAAUUUUAACUUGUCUUUUGCCUGUCUGCCUUAACCUUAAGGGUAGAUAUUUAUCAUUUUCCUUAAGGAGCUGUACAAUAAUCUUUCAUGCUUUUUGUUAGGAACCAUUUACAAUUCCUACUGUCUGCUACUUAUCGUUGUGUUCUACUUGUUCUAGAGUUCUGUCUCCACCUGUCUUCAUUUUUAGGGGUACUGUUUUUUAGGGGUACUAUUUCUCUGUUUGGAAAUGUGAGCGGAUGGCAGUUUCUGCCUCAGCCCUCUUGCUGGGCCAUUGUCUCAUGUGGGUUGUCUGCUGUUCCACAUUUAAGUAAUAGUUAUUUCAGCUUUAUCAAAAGUUUGUAAGUUCCCAGUUCUUCUGGACUUCUGAUUAAUUCAGCCUGAUUUUAUUUAGGGCAAAUGAUUAUGAUCCCCUUUCCAUUUUGUGAAUUUUUCAUAUUUUACCAAUAAAUCUCAUUGCAAUUCUUUGCUUACAAGAUGGCUUGAAAGAUGCAAGCAAUGAUGGAUUGCUCUUUAUUGUUUUAAAAUAUUUAUUGGCCUUAAAUUGCUGAAAUAAUAUGGUUUUUCCAACCUUUGUGUUUUUAUGCAUUUUUAACCCUACGUCUUUAGUGUAUAAUCUUCUGUGAGUCUGUGGUUUCUAUAAGUGUCAGGAAUUUUUCAGGUGUCUUUAUUAUCCUUUGAAAUCAUGAUCUAUUUGGACAAUUCCAUCUUUGUUUGGACUAUACAGUUGACUUGAGUACCUAAGUGAAAUGGAGCAGGUUAGAAAAAAGUAGUUUGUUUUAUAGUAAUGAGAAUUACAUUACAAGUCCCCUGGCAUGUUCCCCUUUGACCUUUUUUGAUGUUUUAAUUUAAGCAUCUCAAACAAGGCAAGAGUUGAUCUCACCAGGCCUUGAAUCCUAUCCAAAAUUGGAUGUUAGGAUAGAUGACACAUACAUUUCUGUAAUACUAAUUAAUAUUGCCAGUUAAUAUUGAUCACUUUCUACAACAUGUCUCUGAGAUAUCUUGCAUCUCCAUGGCAUCUAAUGAGGUGUAUUGUGAAAUAGUUUCAUAUAUUAAAAAUACUGGAAAAUAAUAUAAAAAAUUAGCUGGGCGUGGUGGUGGGCACCUGUAGUCCUAGCUGCUCCGGAGGCUGAGGCAGGAGAAUGGUGUGAACCCAGGAGGUGGAGGCUGCAGUGAGCCGAGAUCGCGCCACUGCACUGCAGCCUGGGCGACAGAGCAAGACUCUGUCAAAAAAAAAAAAAAAAAUGCUGAACUACAAAAUUCAUGCAGUUUGCUUAUAAUCACUCUGAAGCCCACCAUAGGUCUACUCUGGAAGCUCAAGUCUUACUUUUUCUGUGUAUUCACAAGACCAGUCUAUCUGUUUAAGAAUAUAUCUGGCGAUGUAAGUCUGGAAAUACGCACUUAGGUGGUUUUGUUACUUAGAAAUAUUUGUUUCCAAAAAGGAAAAAAAAGGUCAAACAAUUUUUUUUUUUUUGAGGCGGAGUCUCAAUCUGUCACCCAGGCUGGAGUGCAAUGGCACAAUCUUGGCUUACUGCAACCUCCACCUCCCUGUUCAAGUGAUUCUCUUGCCUCAGCCUCCCAAGUAGCUGGGUCUAAAGGUGUACACCACUAUGCCCGGCUUAUUUUUGUAUUUUUAGUAGAUACAGGGUUUCACCAUGUUGGCCAGGCUGAUCUUGAACUCUUGACUGGUGAUCCCCCCUCCUCGGUCUCCCAAAGUGCUGGGAUUACAGGUGUGAGCCACCAAGCCUGGCCGAUCAAACAGAAUUUUUAUAAAGUUGUCUUUAAAAAAAAGAAAAAAAAAGUAUCCAGCUGUUAAACAUUUUCAAAGUGAAGUUAAUCAAUACCCUGUACUUUUAGUUCCUUAAUUCUUUUGAUCUUUGUGCCAUGAUUUUUUACUAUUAGUUAAGAAAGUGUAAUGAACCAAAGAACAAGAAGUAGGGGGAGAAAAGAGUUGCCUGCUUCAUUUGACAAUAGACCAUUUAUCUUCUGUUAUUUGCCUUUCUUAAAGUACGGAGAGUUUUUGGAUUUUUUUCCCCCAGUCACUUUUUGUAGCCUGUAUUUUUUGUUUAUUUUAUUGAAUAAUACAAUUAUUCCCUCAAUAUUUAAUGGGAGCAUUUAUUUUGUCUGCUGAAUUCCAUACUGGUGCAAGAAUUAUAAAACAGCCUCUAGUCUGAAGCUGAUACAGAGAGUGGUUGAACAUUAUUUGUCUCCUAAUCUUUUUAUUAAAGGGGGUUGUAACAUUUGGUGGUUACUCCUUCCUUUAAAAAACAAUUAUAUCUUCAUAUACAAAUUAGGGUAAUUAAAAAAAAACUUUCUGUGGGAAUUUGGGAUCUGUAACAUAUUAAAUGGAAGAGAGUGUAUUUUGUUGAUAUUCACAGGAGUUGGAUAAUUUACUUGUUGCUUUACUAGAUGAGGCCAAGGUGAAGAAAAUGCCCAUUUGUUCUGCAAUUGGCUGAUUAGGCUUCCUUUAAAUAUAAAGCAAGUUACAUAGCAGUUAAGAGUAUUUUAACAUUUUUUUCUUUUAAUAUUAAGGAAUAACACAUAAGUUGGAAAAUUAAUUAGCCGUGUCGAGUAGUAUAAGAGUAUUUUUCUAAUUUCACUUCUGGCAGUUCUGAUAGAAAUCCUUCCCAUGGGUGAGACUCCUUAGGAAAACGUUCUGAGUUCAGAACACUGCUUUAAACUACAUUAUAUUUUUUUUGCUUCUCAAACCAGAUCACACUAUAAAUCCAACCUGAUUUCUAAGUAGAGUAUAGAUGUGGCUUGAGAUAAUGAAUUGAUUUUUGUGGGUUUUUUUUUUUUGUAAUUAGCAAAUAUUUGCUUCGAAAACCUUUUUAUAAAAAAUCAGAAGUUACAUUUUUUCAUUAAAGAACGUUUGAAAAGUUUAGAAAAGGAGGAGAGAGACACAUUACUAAUCUUCCAAACCCAGUCAUGGUUAAUAUUUUCAUAUAUUUACAUAGUUGUUCAUGGUACAUAUAACCAACCAUUUUAUGUUCUGCGUACAGUUUUCCCCAAAUUAUUACGUAGUCUUUAUGAACAUAAUUUUUAAGGUCUGUAUAAUAUUCCAUUGAGUGGAUGUAUGCAGUUUACUUAGGUAUUUUUCAAUUAUUAGAUGUUUCUCUUUUUUUCCCUAUUAUAAAUAAUGCUCUGAUGAAAAUCUUUGUGCAAAAACAAUUUUCCCUUUCUGGUUCAGAAUAUUUCCUUAGAGUAAAUUUCUGAAGAUAAAGUUGCUGGAAUAAAGAUCUCAAUAUUUUUAAGGCUGCUGGGUUUUUUUUUUUUUACUAGAUGAAUACUUUUUUGUUAGUGUGAAAUGUUUAUAUUUGGACAAGAGGGAAGGAAAUCUCUGUUUGCUGACUCAUGUUUUUAUUUUGCACUUUAAACUGAUAAGGCCACUUAGCUUUUGACAUAAACUAAGGCAGGAAGUACAAAAAGGGGCAGAAAAAAAGUAGUUGUCUUGCCAAGGCCAUAGUAUCAUGGACUCAUUUGAGUUCCUUAUAUGAGGUAGGUUACCUGUUUGACUUGUAUAUUAAAAAAUGCUUAACUCAGGUAAAAAUUAGUCAUCAGCCUGCAUUUUGUUUUGUCUGGGCAUGUUUAUAUGCAAAGUGCUGUGAUCUUUCACUUUAAUUUUCGUGAGUGGCCUCAAGACAUUUACCACCUAACUGGCUUCUAUAAUGUUUGGAUGCCCUUGGUUUAGAUUUUUUUUUUUUUUUUUGCUCCCAGUAUGAAGAAAUCUUUCUGUAUUGAAGAUAUUACCUUAGUUGUCUUUCUAAAAUGUAGAUCUAAUAAUGCUAAUUCUCAGAUUUAAAACCUUCCACUUGUCCAUAUGAUAAGAUUCUUCAGUCUUGCCCCUUCCUUCAUAUCAGCUUGUAUCAUCAUCUCCAGCGGAUUAAACCCUAGCAUUUCUAUCAUGUGUCUGUUGGAACAAGCCAUUUGGAAAAGUGGUUUAAAAAUUCUGGCUCUAGAGCCAGGCAAAAUGGGUUCAGAUCCAGGUUCUGCCACUUAUAGCUGUCUACAUAACUUUGGACAAGAUACUCAACUAUUCUAUAUUUUAUUUUCCUUACAUGUAAAAUAAAGAAAAUGAUAGUAUUUACUUCACAGUAAAUACUAAGGUAUUGUUGCUAAGAUUAAACUGGUUAAUAGAUAAACAGCAGUGAACAGUGUUUGUCAAGUAAUGAACACACAAAAUGUUUGCUCUAUUGUUUUGCAAAAUUCUACUUAUCCUUUAAGUCUGAUGUUUUCUCUUGGAAAAAAAUGUUCUGAAAUCUCUGGAAUUGUUCUUUCCUUUUCCGUUUUUAUAUAUUAUUGUCUUAGUUUGUAGGCCGCUAUAACAAAAUACCAUAUAGACUGAGUGGCUUAUAAACAACAGAAAUUUAUUUCUCAAAGUUACAGUAACUGGGAAAUCCAAGAUCAAGGUACCUGGAUGGCCUCUUCUCUCUGUAACCUCAUAUGGUGGAAGGGAGGAGAGAUCUCUCUGGGAUCUCUUUUAUGAGGGCACUAAUUCCAUUUAUGGGAGCUCCGUCCUCAUGACCUAAUCACCUCCCAAAGGACUCACCUUCUAAUUCUGUCACCUUUGGGGUUAGGAUUUCAACAUGUGAAUUUAGGGAGGGGAUACAAAUAUUCAGACCAGAGUGUUGUUGAUACUUGUUUUAUAGCCUUUAUCACAUGAUAUUAGAGUAAGUUAAUAGUAGGUAAAUGCACAGCACAUGGGCCUCUUCUUCGGUUAUUCUUGUGCCCAUGGGCAAUGGUAUAAUCGUAUUAUUUCUUCUGACUGAGUCCCUGGAAGGUCACCUAAUAAAACAUCUCAGCAAAGUCCUUUAGAAUUAGCAUGCAGGUUAGCAAUUUGCUUUAUGGGAGUUAGUUGUUUACACACUGGCUUUCCCAAUGGAUUGUGAGCUCCUCCAGUAUGUUAGACAUGUUUGCUUCUGUGUCUCCUGUGUCUAGCACUGUGCUAGGCAUACUUAGCAGGUGCUUAAUACAGCUUUGUUGAAUGAAUGUCGAUUUGAAUAGUUAAAACAAAAAUCUGAAAUGGUGGUUCUUAUAUAAUACGUUGCCCAACACUUGCCUUAAAUAAAUACCCCCAAGUGAUUUUGGGGGUAUUUGUUUAAAUGUAUUUGUUAUAUAUUUUAAAAUAGCCCCAAGUUAUUUUGAUGCAAACUUAGCCAUUCUGUUUAAAAAUUAUUGCUUAAAAUGUUAAAAAGCUGUUUUUGAAGAAGAGAUGGACAUAUAGAAUAUGAAGAAAUACACUCCCUCUAUAAAUUAUUCCCAGAAGCCUAGAAAAAAGUUCUUGUUCUUUUGCAAAACUAACCUUUUAGUAAAAGGAAAUUAUCAUAUCAAUAGGUACACUCUGACCAAGUGUGACUUUUGAUAAUAGCAUAGUUUUGUUUUCUCUUUCCUUUAAUGUUAAAUGAAAAUAAUACCAACUUCAAAAAAACUAGUAAAUUUGGGUGAACUCUUUAAAAAGGAAAACAGCGGACACCCUGUGGCCUCCCAAAUAGAGUUGACGCUCCGUAUUUGGCUUUCUAAGUUCUUCAAGGAGCUAAAUUAUUCAUCAGGCAUUUAGUGAGAAUCAGCUAUGUGCCAGGUACUAUGCCAAGUUCCAAAGGUAAGAAAAUAAUAAGUUGGAGUCCUACAUUGUUUCCUGUAGUGAAGAUGACAGAUGUGUAGAUUAUCACAAUGUAGCUAUAGACAUGCACCGUUUGCCAUGACAGCUAUUUAUAAUAAUUAUAAUUUUUAAUUUCUGAGGCUAACGAUUUCCCCAUUCUGAUCCAUUUAUUGGUAAUUUGUGCCUUCUCUUUUUUAUUUAUCAGUUUUGCUAGGGAUUUAUCCAAUUUUAUUAGUAUUUUCAAAGAAUCAACUUUGAUUUUAUAGGUUUUCUUUAGUAUGCUUUAAAUUUCUGCUUUCAUUUUCUUCUACUUUCUUUGGGUUUAUUUUUCCUUUUAAAAAAUCUUUGGCGGGUAUUAGAGUGUUAGUUUUCAGCUUUUUUCCUUUUCUAAUAUAUGCAUUUAAGACUAUAAAUUUCCCUCUGUGCCUUGAGCCACAUCCUGCAUUUUUGAUGUGAUAUUUUUACAAUCAUUCAGUUAAAAAUAUUUUCUAUUUCCUCUAUAAUUUCUUCUUUGACCUUUGGGUUAUUUUAAAGUUUGGUUCUUUUCAAUAACAAUGUUUUUAUUGAUUUAGUUAUACUAAAAUCAAAGAAUAUGUUCUAUAUGAUUUUAGUAUUUUGAUACAGAUUGAGAUUUGCUUUGUUAUUCAUUAUAUGGUCAAUUUCAGUAAGUAUUCCUUGCGUAUUUGAAAGUGUUAUGAAUUGUACAGUUGUUGAGUGCUGUGAUAAUAUGUAUAUGAAUUGGAUCAAGUUUUUAAACAAUUUUUUUCUGUAUCUAUUGAUUUUUGUUUGCUUGUUUUAUCAUUUAUUAUGUUAAUCUCCCACUAGGAUUGUGGGUUUGCCUGUCAUUGUAAUUGUUAGUCUUUUGCUUUAUGAAUUUGAGACUGUUAUUAUUUACAUAAAAUUUGGAAUUUAAAAACUACAUGGUGGCUCAACUCAUCACUAUAAAAUGUCCUUUUUUUCUUUUUUGUCUUUAAAAAUCUCUGGUGAUACCUCUUACUUUUGAAGUCUGUUUUAUCUGAAUGGAUAGCUAUGCCAGCUUUUUGGGUGGAAUAUGCAUAGUAUAUAUUUUUCCACUCUCUUGCUUUCAAUACUGUGUUCUUAUAUUUAAUGUGUGUCUCUUUUAAGUACAAUAUGGUUAAAUAAUGUUCCCCACAACUCUCUUAGUUGUCAUAUUUUAGUCAUUUAUAUUUAAGUAAUUGCUUAUACUUUGGGAUUAUAUCUAAAUCUUACUAUUUUCUGUUUGUCUCAUCUGUUGUCUCCUUUUCAUAUGUUUUGCAUUAAUCAUUUUUAAAAUUUUUAUUUGAUUUUUAGAGACGCUCUCACUCUGUCACUCAGGUUGGAGUGCAGUGGCACAAUCAUAACACCUAUCAUAACUCCUAGGCUCAAGCAGUCCUCCUGCCUCUGCCCCCUGAGUGGCUGAGACUGCAGGCACAUGCCACCUUGCUGGACUACUUUUUUACUUUUUGUAGAGAUAGGGUCUUCCUGUGCUGCCCAGGCUACUCUGGAACUCCUCAAGCUAUCCUUCUACCUUGGCUUCCCAGAGUGCUGGGAUUACUGGGCUAAUCAUAUAUAUUUUUUUAAUUCCAUAUUUUUAACCCAUCUAUUAGCUUGUUAUAAUUUUUAACUUAUUCUCUCAGUUGUUGCUUUAUUAUGACAUGAAUUCAUAACUUACUGUACUAAUAGUAAAUUAUACUUUACCAUGGCCUGGAUAACACAAGGACCUUAGAAUGCUAACUUCAUAUAUCUCUUUUUGCUGUUGCCAUGCAUUUUAAUUGUACAUAUAUUUUAAACAUCACAAGACAUUCCUAUUGUUGUUUUGUGAAGUCAGUAUUCAUUUAAACUUACCCUUAUUUCCCCUUCAGGAGCUCUUCCUCAUUUCCUGCAGUUCUUUGCUUAUUUCUAGAGUCUUUUUCCUUCUGCCUGAAGAAUUCCUGUUAGUAUUUCUUUUAGUGACAAUCUGCUGUAAACCAGUUCUCUCAGAUUUUGAUUGUUGGAAAGCAUCUUUAUUUCACAAUCAUUUUUUGAAUGUGUUUUUCCUCUAAAUGUAGAAUUUUAAGUUACCAGCUAUUUACGUUUGGCACUAAUGAUGUCAUUUCAUUGUCUUCUGGUUUCCAUUGUUUAUGCUGAAAUGUCAGCUGUCAACCUGAUUGUACUUACUUGAAGGUAAUGUGCCUUUUUAAAGAGUUUCAUCUUAGGUUUUCAAGAAUUUUACUGUUAUAUGACACAUUGAAAUUUGUGGAUUUCUCUGUAUGUAUCCUUGGAAGGUGUAGGGCUUCGUGAAUGUAUGGUUAGAUGUCUGUUGACAGUUUUGGAAAAAUCCUUGGCUAGUAUCUAAAAAUAUUGCUCUGUUACAGUCUUUCUUCUUUUCCUUUAAGACUCUACUUAUGCAGUGCUAGACCUUUCACUAGAGCCAUUAUGUCUCCUUAGUUCUUUAUUUUUCAUUUUUUCCCUCUCUUUGCAUUAGUAUGAGCAUUUUUUACCAGUCUUCCUGCUCACUAAUCUUUUAUUCUACUGUAUUUAACCUGUUGUUAAGUUCAUCCUAUUUAAAGUCUCAUUAGUUAUAUUUUUCAGUUCUAGAAUUUUUAUUUCAUUCUUCUUUAUGGAUUCCAGUUCUCUGUUAAAAUCUUCAACCUUGUCUUCUCUUUCCUUGACAUAGUAAAUAGUAAUCAUUAAUACUUUAAAGUCUGUUUCUGGUAACUCCAUUACCUGGGUCACCCGUUAGGUCUGUUUCUAUUCUGUUUUGUUUUGAUCAUUUGGUCCUGUUUCUUGGUAUGCUUGAUAACUUUUGGUUCAUUGCAUACACUGUGAAUUUAAAAUUGUAGUGGCUAAGGUUGAUGUUGUCUUCCUCUACAGAGAAUUUGUUUUUCUUCUGGCAAGCUGUUAGAGAGCAAUACCCAUCACCUAGACCAAGGCUAGGAUUAAGAUGAUUCUAGAUUGGUUGUAAAGACUGAUCCGUUUCAUUUUUGCCCUUAGACUGGGGCAUAUUCCUCCAGGAGCUUCCAUUGAAAGCCUAGACUAUUUACCAGGGUUUCUCCUCAGCAGGCCCUCAACUCCAUUUGUUGCUGUGUUGUUAUUUUGGGGUUCCUCAGCGCUAUGAGGCUACUAGAAGCUCUGCUUAGUUUUUAGCCUCUUAGUUACCUCUUUCUGCUCGGCUCCUAGACCUUUUGCUGCUCAUAGCAUAGCUAUUGGCAAAUCCCUGGAAAGAGUGGUGACGAAUAUUCAGCUCACUUCAUUGCAUUUCCCCUCUCUCCAGGAUCUUGGCCCCCUCAAGUCCUGAGUGCCUUGGUUCCUCUUUGAUGCCUUUAAAAAGCUGGGCUUUUGUUUGUUUGUUUUCUGGCUUGUUUGUUUGGAAGGAGGUUGGUCUGAUACGUGCUACUCCAGUUUAGCCAGGGUUUGUACAAAGUUAACCUCCUUAACCUUUUUCACAUUUUAUGUUUUCAUGUGCUAAAGAGUAAACAGUUUAAAUGAGGCAACUUGGCUAAAGAAUUUGGUACAGUGCUGACUGGGUUACUUUUUUAAACACUAGGAAUGGUAAUUUCUACUCUUCUGGACUUCAAACUAAGAAGUUAAAGAGACUUCUCUGUAAAUAAACAAAUCUCUUCUGCUGUCCUUUUGCAUUUGGAGACAGCUUUAUUUCACCAUAUCCAAGGAGUAUAACUAGUGCUGUCAUUAUGAAUGUGACAAGUUUAUUUUCCUUUACAAGUCCAGCUGUGAAGAGACUUCUUGGGUGGAAACAGGGCGAUGAAGAAGAAAAAUGGGCAGAGAAAGCUGUUGAUGCUUUGGUGAAAAAACUGAAGAAAAAGAAAGGUGCCAUGGAGGAACUGGAAAAGGCCUUGAGCUGCCCAGGGCAACCGAGUAACUGUGUCACCAUUCCCCGCUCUCUGGAUGGCAGGCUGCAAGUCUCCCACCGGAAGGGACUGCCUCAUGUCAUUUACUGCCGUGUGUGGCGCUGGCCCGAUCUUCAGAGCCACCAUGAACUAAAACCACUGGAAUGCUGUGAGUUUCCUUUUGGUUCCAAGCAGAAGGAGGUCUGCAUCAAUCCCUACCACUAUAAGAGAGUAGAAAGCCCUGUACUUCCUCCUGUGCUGGUUCCAAGACACAGCGAAUAUAAUCCUCAGCACAGCCUCUUAGCUCAGUUCCGUAACUUAGGACAAAAUGAGCCUCACAUGCCACUCAACGCCACUUUUCCAGAUUCUUUCCAGCAACCCAACAGCCACCCGUUUCCUCACUCUCCCAAUAGCAGUUACCCAAACUCUCCUGGGAGCAGCAGCAGCACCUACCCUCACUCUCCCACCAGCUCAGACCCAGGAAGCCCUUUCCAGAUGCCAGCUGAUACGCCCCCACCUGCUUACCUGCCUCCUGAAGACCCCAUGACCCAGGAUGGCUCUCAGCCGAUGGACACAAACAUGAUGGCGCCUCCCCUGCCCUCAGAAAUCAACAGAGGAGAUGUUCAGGCGGUUGCUUAUGAGGAACCAAAACACUGGUGCUCUAUUGUCUACUAUGAGCUCAACAAUCGUGUGGGUGAAGCGUUCCAUGCCUCCUCCACAAGUGUGUUGGUGGAUGGUUUCACUGAUCCUUCCAACAAUAAGAACCGUUUCUGCCUUGGGCUGCUCUCCAAUGUUAACCGGAAUUCCACUAUUGAAAACACCAGGCGGCAUAUUGGAAAAGGAGUUCAUCUUUAUUAUGUUGGAGGGGAGGUGUAUGCCGAAUGCCUUAGUGACAGUAGCAUCUUUGUGCAAAGUCGGAACUGCAACUACCAUCAUGGAUUUCAUCCUACUACUGUUUGCAAGAUCCCUAGUGGGUGUAGUCUGAAAAUUUUUAACAACCAAGAAUUUGCUCAGUUAUUGGCACAGUCUGUGAACCAUGGAUUUGAGACAGUCUAUGAGCUUACAAAAAUGUGUACUAUACGUAUGAGCUUUGUGAAGGGCUGGGGAGCAGAAUACCACCGCCAGGAUGUUACUAGCACCCCCUGCUGGAUUGAGAUACAUCUGCACGGCCCCCUCCAGUGGCUGGAUAAAGUUCUUACUCAAAUGGGUUCACCUCAUAAUCCUAUUUCAUCUGUAUCUUAAAUGGCCCCAGGCAUCUGCCUCUGGAAAACUAUUGAGCCUUGCAUGUACUUGAAGGAUGGAUGAGUCAGACACGAUUGAGAACUGACAAAGGAGCCUUGAUAAUACUUGACCUCUGUGACCAACUGUUGGAUUCAGAAAUUUAAACAAAAAAAAAAAAAAACACACACACCUUGGUAACAUACUGUUGAUAUCAAGAACCUGUUUAGUUUACAUUGUAACAUUCUAUUGUAAAAUCAACUAAAAUUCAGACUUUUAGCAGGACUUUGUGUACAGUUAAAGGAGAGAUGGCCAAGCCAGGGACAAAUUGUCUAUUAGAAAACGGUCCUAAGAGAUUCUUUGGUGUUUGGCACUUUAAGGUCAUCGUUGGGCAGAAGUUUAGCAUUAAUAGUUGUUCUGAAACGUGUUUUAUCAGGUUUAGAGCCCAUGUUGAGUCUUCUUUUCAUGGGUUUUCAUAAUAUUUUAAAACUAUUUGUUUAGCGAUGGUUUUGUUCGUUUAAGUAAAGGUUAAUCUUGAUGAUAUACAUAAUAAUCUUUCUAAAAUUGUAUGCUGACCAUACUUGCUGUCAGAAUAAUGCUAGGCAUAUGCUUUUUGCUAAAUAUGUAUGUACAGAGUAUUUGGAAGUUAAGAAUUGAUUAGACUAGUGAAUUUAGGAGUAUUUGAGGUGGGUGGGGGGAAGAGGGAAAUGACAACUGCAAAUGUAGACUAUACUGUAAAAAUUCAGUUUGUUGCUUUAAAGAAACAAACUGAUACCUGAAUUUUGCUGUGUUUCCAUUUUUUAGAGAUUUUUAUCAUUUUUUUCUCUCUCGGCAUUCUUUUUUCUCAUACUCUUCAAAAAGCAGUUCUGCAGCUGGUUAAUUCAUGUAACUGUGAGAGCAAAUGAAUAAUUCCUGCUAUUCUGAAAUUGCCUACAUGUUUCAAUACCAGUUAUAUGGAGUGCUUGAAUUUAAUAAGCAGUUUUUACGGAGUUUACAGUACAGAAAUAGGCUUUAAUUUUCAAGUGAAUUUUUUGCCAAACUUAGUAACUCUGUUAAAUAUUUGGAGGAUUUAAAGAACAUCCCAGUUUGAAUUCAUUUCAAACUUUUUAAAUUUUUUUGUACUAUGUUUGGUUUUAUUUUCCUUCUGUUAAUCUUUUGUAUUCACUUAUGCUCUCGUACAUUGAGUACUUUUAUUCCAAAACUAGUGGGUUUUCUCUACUGGAAAUUUUCAAUAAACCUGUCAUUAUUGCUUACUUUGAUUAAAAA